CUCCCCGCCUCCCCUUCCCUCCCCUCCUGGCGGGUGCGGGGCCGGUGUCCGAAGUCAGGCGGCGGCCCCCGCAGCGGCCGCAGGAGGGGCGGCUGCGGUGGGCGCCGCGGGCGAUGCCCCUGCCCGGCUGCUCCGGCGGGGGGCAGUGCGAGCGGCGGCGGCGGGGGAGGAGGCGGGGGGCGGCGGCUGCGGCGGCUGCAGCAGAGGGGCCGAGAGCUGGCGGUGGCGGCGGCGGUGGUCGUGAAGGGCAUCGGCGGCGGCGGUGAUGGCAGAGAUGAUGUGAGUGCCCGCCGGCUGGAGACCUGGGGCCGCGGAGCGCGGGACGGGCGGCGGCGGCGUGCGGGAGCGGCCCCGGGGGCGGCGGAGGGAUGCGGGGAGCGCGGGCAGAGCCGGAGCGGCGGCCGCCAACCGGCCGGCAGUGGCUGGAGCCCCGCGCUGCGGCGCCGGGGGAGCCGGGCCCGGCGUGGGGGUCGCGGGCGGCGGCGGGGCGGUCAGGCCGAGGGGCGUCUGCGAUUGUUCUCAACACCCCUCCCCCACCCCAUCCCGUGUGUCUGUUUGUUACUUGCAGCUGAAGAUGGAAAGAGCCAGGCGAAGGGGAGGCGGCGGCGGCCGCGGCCGCGGAGGCAAGAAUGUAGGGGGCUCUGGCCUAAGCAAGAGUAGACUCUAUCCCCAGGCCCAGCACUCCCACUACCCCCACUACGCGGCCUCAGCCACCCCUAAUCAGGCCGGGGGCGCAGCCGAAAUCCAGGAGCUGGCCUCCAAACGAGUGGACAUCCAGAAAAAGAGGUUUUACCUAGACGUGAAGCAAAGCUCCCGGGGCCGCUUCCUAAAGAUAGCCGAAGUCUGGAUAGGGAGAGGCCGGCAGGACAACAUCAGAAAGAGUAAACUGACCCUCUCCCUGUCUGUGGCAGCGGAGCUGAAGGACUGUCUAGGGGACUUCAUCGAGCACUAUGCCCACCUGGGCCUGAAAGGCCACCGGCAAGAGCAUGGCCACAGCAAAGAGCAAGGCUCCAGAAGGAGGCAGAAGCACUCGGCACCCUCCCCACCAGUCUCGGUGGGGUCCGAAGAGCAUCCUCACAGUGUCCUGAAAACAGACUAUAUCGAGAGGGACAAUAGGAAAUAUUACCUAGACCUAAAGGAAAAUCAGCGGGGUCGCUUCCUACGGAUUAGACAAACCAUGAUGCGGGGGACUGGCAUGAUAGGUUAUUUUGGCCACAGUUUGGGCCAAGAACAGACUAUUGUCCUCCCAGCACAAGGAAUGAUUGAGUUUCGUGAUGCCUUGGUUCAGCUGAUUGAAGACUAUGGCGAAGGAGACAUAGAAGAACGAAGAGGUGGAGACGAUGACCCGCUUGAACUCCCAGAGGGGACUUCUUUCAGAGUGGACAAUAAAAGGUUCUACUUUGAUGUGGGCUCUAAUAAAUAUGGAAUUUUCCUGAAGCUCACAAAUUACCCCAAAUCCAGAGAGAAUAUCAACCUUUUUCACUGUUGUCAAAUCAAGCAUAAGGAACAGCCCCAUGAUACUACAAAAACAGUUGAGGAAUAAGGAAUAAAUCUCUUAUGUUACACCUCAGAAUAAAGGCAUUCGGUGAAAGAAAUGAACUGAAGUUCAUCAUGAAUGUAAGGCCUCAGUACUUGACAUUCCUCCACGGAAGGGAAGACAAGUAUCAACACCACUGGCAUCAUUUCCAAACUGAUCUUAUGUUGAAUAAUUUCCACCACAUUGAAGUACCUUUCGACUCUAUCCAGUUUUUGGGUUUUGUUUUUUUUAAUUCAUCAAGCCUUUCGUUUUCAAACCACCAUUUGUCAGCCUUGAGGUAGAGAGACAUAUAGAUUUGAAAAUACUUUCUUAAGAGAUCAUGUAACUAUAUAACUCUGAAUUUAAAAAUUGAGGGGGGAGGGAUAAUUUCAACCCACUGCCUCUUACCAGAAACAUUUUUUUAAAUCUGUAACUGCUUUAGUGUUAACAGGGUGCAAGGUGGUUUUUGUCCCGUAUUGUUCUUAAAAGGUUCUCAUUUAUUGUGAUUGUAUUGUACUGUAUGAGAACAAAUCAUAAAUUGCCUUGUAUUGUUUAUAAUAGACCAUACCACGUACUACUUCAGUUUUUAUGUUCCAAGUUUUUCAGUGAUGCAUGUUAACAGUUAGGUCCUAAAAUUCUGUGGUGCUAAUUCUCCCAUACCCAAUGGUGCUUUUGUGGAUGCUAACUGCACACAUGCUGAACAAAGCUUGAAGUUUAAAACUUUCCUCCCUUCCUCUGUUUAUAUGAAGUAAAAUGAAAUAACUUGAAUUUGUCUCAAAGUAUCACUGACAAUCUAAUAAACUUGUUUAUAUGUGUGA